AUUUUGUGGCCCGCUAUGGCGGCGGUGUUGAGGUUGGGUACGGGAUGCGGGGUCUUUGACUGAAGGGGUAGGCCAAGUGGAGGUAUCAGGGACGUCGCGCGGCACAGAAGAGGACCAGCCUGGACGCCGGGGACGCUGUCAUGUACGGCGCGAGCGGGGGCCGCGCCAAACCCGAGAGGAAAAGCGGCGCGAAGGAGGAGGCCGGGCCAGGCGGUGCCGGCGGUGGGGGCAGCCGAGUGGAGCUCUUGGUUUUCGGCUAUGCCUGCAAGCUGUUCCGGGACGACGAGCGGGCCCUGGCUCAGGAACAGGGACAGCACCUCAUCCCCUGGAUGGGGGACCACAAGAUCCUCAUCGACAGGUCGGUUCCUCUCCCCACCCGUCGAUCCUUCCCUUCCCUCACCCGCUUGAUCUCGUCUGAUGUUGACUUGACUGCAAGGACUGCAGAGAGUUUUCUGGAGCCAGCGGGGAUCUGGGGGACACCCCCUCCCCUGUCCCCACCUCCUCCUGGUGUUCUGGUGGGGAGGGGGACGGUGAAACCUGCCCUAAGGCACUGGCUGGAAUUGCGUGCCGCGUCCGUCUCCGGAGGGAUCGUCUCUGGUCCCGCAGCCCCUCUCGACCCCUCACCCUGUCGCUGGGCUGCAGUUGGCGAUUCCGCGCGGUGAAAGCAGCCAGUGCCCAGGGUCUUUUCCUGAGUGCACCUGGGCCUGCCGCCCGGCGAUGCCAUGGGGUCGUGCGCUGCUUUUCUACUUGCCGCGCUCUCACUGCUCGGUGUACUGGGAGGGUACCCUGGGAGGCGUGCCUUUAUUCUUCCGAACCGCCGCUCACUGAGACAGUGGCUAGAAGUGUCUCUUGGACCUGUGAGUUAGCCUUAACCUGUUAUGCCCCCAGAGCCCUCAGUGGAGCGCCCGUACUUUGCCGGCAUGACGUUUGAUUUCCCGGUGAUAAUCCGACGAGUUUGACAGAUUGAGGUAGUGAGCAAAGUUGCCCGUCAGUUGGUGGCCACUUGACUUCGUGCGGACCCUGGCCUUGCUCUUGGAAGAGAUAGUGUUCUUAGGGCUGGUUUCACUGUCUCUUAAGACUGAAGGGUGGAGCUGGGAUAUAGAUGUGUUGUUUCUUUUCAAAUCAAACCUGCUUUAGGUCGUCACUCGAGGGUGUCUAGCGAUUAUGGGCAGUGGGGGCCUGGGAUUAGGGAUUUCUAAAGGCGUUUGAUUUGAAAAGGAUAACAUUACAUGAUGUAGGUGGUUUGCUCCCCUCUUUCUUCCCAUUUUUUCAAUCCCCCUUCCCCUCGUCUCUGGGUUUUGGGGUUGUUGUGGGGUGGUUUUUUUUCUUUUUUGCCUGUUCGGCUACUUCUGGGGCCCGGACUGAAAAGCUAACCAUGACCAACCAUUAAACUGUGGAAUAGUCUCUCCACGUGAAGAAAGCCCAUCGUUUGAGACCAUUAAAACUGGAUUCUUCAUAGCCCUGGAGCAUGACUGUAGGGAUGACCUCUGAGCUGGCCAGAAUGGACACAUUAAUGACCAAAUAGGCCUUUUUCCAUCCCUGACGUUUCCUUUUGGAAUUAGAGCUCGAAAACGAGAACUGGUGAAGGGAGGGCCGCGGAAUCAGAUCAUGUCUGGAUCUGAUGGCUCCGUGCUGUGCUCAAGCGUGCUGUGCCUUCACACCAUGGUUUAUAUUGAAUGUGUCGCCUGAGUUGUCAGGCUUGCUUUUCCAAAGUGUCACUUGUGUUAUUUAUCAUUAAAGUUUGGUAAGCAAUGAAGUCUGAGCUCUUUGUACAGUUUUCCUAUCAUUCUGUACAUGAUUUGAGUUAGGUCUUCCAAAACUGGUGGGGAGCAAACGCCGCACAUGUACAUGUAUAAUAUUUUUAAUAAUAAUCUACAUUUGUAAGUUAAGGAGGUUUACAUCAAAAUCCAAUUAAUUUUGAAAUUUAAUGAAAUGCAGUAACUUGACUACCUUGGAAUUUUGGGCCUUUUUCCUGUAAAUGUCUUUUUUGGUCUACAUUAAUAUUUUUGGUUCCCAUUACAAAAGUCAGCAUUAAAAAAAUAAGCAGACUUUUGUUUGUUUCUCUACAUUUGUUUUUGAAACCCUAAACCUGAGUGUUUUAAGUAAAGUUCACUAACUCAUUCAUUUAUUAUCUGACAGUUACACGUUGACAGCAUCCUCAUUGAAUCCUUUAUGUUAAAAGCAUAGCAGAAAGUGCUCCCAUUACUUAUUUGGCCAAACUACUGUUUGGUCCAUGCAAGAGAAACAUGGAAGUGUCUUCAUGUAUGUUAUUUCCUUGAGGGUAUAAAGUUCAGAAGGAAAUAUUGAUACCAUAUCUUCUAAUAGUUUUGCUCUGUUCCCAGUGAACCUCCUUAAACUGCAUGUAUAUGUCACUGUUCCAAUGUAUGUGUGUCUCUCUAUCACGUAACCCAGCACUUAUUUCCUCAGCCAAGUGGCUAGGGGGCGAGCCUAGCCAAGAUUUUACCUCCAAUGGACGCAAGUUUCUUUGGUGAAGAUCUCUCCUGAGAGUUCGGGACUAGCAGAAAGAAGCGAGGAAAUUUCGACCGUUUGGUUCUUACGGAUAGGUAUUUAUGUAUUUGGUUUGUGUGAAUGUAAGCUAUGAUAUUUAACUUUUCAGAAAAAAAUAAUAAUUUUUUGCAAGUGGCAUUGAAUGGUUGACCAAACCAUAAUGGUAAGAACUGCCAGUGAAGUGGGUACCAUUUUUGCUAUUAAUGGAUUGUUUGCCUUUAGUUAUAAAUGUUAUCUUACUGUGGAAAGGAAUUUAGAGUUUGUUAAGAUAACUUGAGUUUAAAAGUAGGUGAGAUAUGACUAUCCAAAUUAAAUAUAAAUCUGGGAAGAGUUUUUAUACUUGUUUUAAUAUUUUUGUUUAUUUUAAUCGGUAAGUAUGUGUGUGUAUAUAUAUAUACAUAUAUAAAACAUCACACACGCACACCAGUCUAGACGUUAAUUUCCUUUUAUUGACCAGCUUGUUCACAUUACAGAUAUGAUGGACGUGGUCACCUGCAUGACCUUUCUGAGUACGAUGCUGAGUAUUCCACGUGGAACAGAGAUUAUCAGCUGUCUGAAGAGGAGGCGCGAAUAGAGGCCCUGUGUGAUGAAGAGAGAGGAAGAAUACAAGCGAUUGAGUGAAGCACUAGCAGAGGAUGGGAGCUACAAUGCCGUGGGGUUCACUUACGGUAGCGACUAUUACGACCCGUCAGAGCCGACGGAGGAGGAGGAGCCUUCCAAACAGAGAGAAAAAAAUGAGGCCGAAAAUUUAGAGGAAAAUGAAGAGCCCUUCGUUGCCCCCUUAGGAUUGAGCGUCCCGUCUGACGUGGAGUUGCCACCAACCGCUAAAAUGCACGCCAUCAUCGAGCGCACGGCCAGCUUCGUGUGCAGGCAGGGAGCACAGUUUGAGAUCAUGCUGAAGGCCAAGCAGGCCCGGAACUCCCAGUUUGACUUUCUGCGCUUCGACCACUACCUCAACCCCUACUAUAAGUUCAUCCAGAAAGCCAUGAAAGAGGGACGCUACACUGUCCUGGCAGAAAACAAAAGUGACGAGAAAAAAAAAUCAGGAGUCAGCUCUGACAAUGAAGAUGAUGAUGAUGAAGAAGAUGGGAAUUACCUUCAUCCCUCUCUCUUUGCCUCCAAGAAGUGUAACCGCCUUGAAGAGCUGAUGAAGCCCUUGAAGGUAGUGGACCCAGAUCAUCCCCUCGCAGCACUUGUUCGUAAGGCACAGGCUGACAGUUCCACUCCCACCCCACACAACGCAGACGGUGCGCCUGUGCAGCCCUCCCAGGUGGAGUACACGGCAGACUCGACCGUGGCAGCCAUGUAUUACAGCUACUACAUGCUACCGGACGGCACUUACUGCCUGGCGCCGCCCCCUCCCGGAAUCGACGUGACUACUUACUACAGCACCCUUCCUGCUGGCGUGACCGUGUCUAACUCCCCUGGAGUGACGACCACCGCCCCACCACCUCCUGGGACCACACCACUACCGCCCCCAACCACAGCAGAGACUAGCAGCGGGGCCACCUCCACAACCACCACCACAAGUGCACUUGCCCCCGUGGCCGCCAUCAUCCCCCCGCCCCCCGACGUCCAGCCCGUGAUUGACAAGCUGGCCGAGUAUGUCGCCAGGAACGGCCUGAAGUUCGAGACCAGUGUUCGUGCCAAGAAUGAUCAAAGAUUUGAGUUCCUGCAGCCGUGGCACCAGUAUAAUGCUUAUUAUGAGUUUAAGAAGCAGUUCUUCCUCCAGAAAGAAGGGGGCGAUAGCAUGCAGGCUGUGUCUGCACCAGAAGAGGCUCCCACAGACUCUGCUCCCGAGAAGCCAAGUGAUGCUGGGGAGGAUGGCGCGCCUGAAGACGCAGCCGAGGUGGGAGCACGGGCAGGCUCAGGCGGGAAGAAGGAGGCAUCGUCCAGUAAGACCGUCCCGGACGGGAAGCUGGUGAAAGCUUCCUUUGCUCCAAUAAGCUUUGCAAUCAAGGCCAAAGAAAAUGAUCUGCUUCCCCUGGAAAAAAAUCGUGUUAAGCUAGAUGAUGACAGUGAUGAUGAUGAAGAAAGCAAAGAAGGCCAAGAAAGUUCUAGUAGUGCUGCAAACACUAACCCAGCAGUUGCCCCACCCUGUGUAGUUGUUGAGGAGAAGAAGCCUCAACUUACCCAGGAGGAGCUAGAAGCAAAGCAAGCAAAGCAAAAGCUGGAAGAUCGCCUCGCAGCUGCUGCCCGGGAAAAGCUGGCCCAGGCGUCUAAGGAGUCAAAAGAGAAACAGCUUCAAGCAGAACGUAAAAGGAAAGCGGCGUUAUUUUUACAGACCCUCAAAAAUCCUCUGCCGGAAGCAGAAGCUGGGAAAAUUGAGGAGAGUCCUUUCAGUGUCGAGGAAUCCAGCACUACGCCCUGCCCUCUACUGACUGGAGGCAGGCCUCUGCCUACUUUAGAAGUUAAACCACCCGAUAGGCCUUCGAGCAAAAGCAAAGAUCCACCGAGAGAAGAAGAGAAAGAAAAGAAAAAGAAAAAGCACAAAAAAAGAUCUCGAACAAGAUCACGUUCUCCCAAGUACCAUUCGUCAUCCAAGUCCAGGUCUAGAUCACACUCAAAAGCAAAGCAUUCUCUUCCCAGUGCCUAUCGGACAGUGCGGCGGUCGAGAGUCACAGCCUCCCCAGGGACGCUGCGCGCGGAGCCCUGUCAGAGCAGCGCGUCAGUGACAGCGGCAGCCGAGCCAGGAAGUUAUCAGGCAGCCUCGACCACCACCAGAUUUGACUCCGCGAGCUCUUUUGAGGGAAAACCUGGUAAAACGUCAAGGUCCCGCUCCCGGUCCCCUCGGAGGAGAGCCCACUCCCCUGAGAGACGGAGGGAAGAGAGGAGUGUGCCCACUGCCUACCGCGUGAGCCGCAGCCCUGGGGCCAGUAGGAAGCGGACCCGCUCCAGAAGUCCCCACGAGAAGAAGAAGAAGAGGCGGUCCCGGUCGCGGACCAAGUCCAAGGCCAGGUCUCAGUCGGUGUCACCCAGCAAGCAGGCAGCGCCCCGGCCCGCGGCCCCCGCGGCCCACUCGGCGCACUCAGCCAGCGUCUCCCCUGUGGAGAGUCGGGGCUCCAGCCAGGAGCGCUCCAGGGGAGUCUCUCAGGAAAAAGAAGCCCAGAUCUCUUCAGCAAUCGUUUCUUCCGUGCAGAGCAAAAUCACUCAGGAUCUCAUGGCCAAAGUCAGAGCGAUGCUUGCAGCUUCCAAAAACCUGCAAACCAGCGCUUCCUGAGACGGGGCCAGCGGAGGCAGAGCCGGGAGGCUGCGUGGGCUUCUGGGCAGGCUCACGCAGACGCCGGCCACACCAUCCACCUGGCCGCCUCCAUGGACCCUUGGUGGCUUUUGUAAAUUAAUUUUUGAUGACAUUUUGAGUUUUAAGAUUUCUGACCAGCAGUCUCUUACCUGUAUAUUUGUAAAUAUAUCAUGUUUCUGUGAAAAUGUAUUAUGAAAUAAAAUGGGAGGAAACACCUUUUCUAGCUAGA